AGCGCCGGACGAGGCCCAGCCAGUCUGGGUCUGGCCUGGCCGCCCCUCCAGCCUGCUGGAGCCGGAGCCGGAGCCGGAGCCGGAGCCGGAGCCGGAGCCAGAGCCAGAGCUCGAGGACUCACCGGCCCAGUCUCCGUCCGGGAUGGGGCCCCGCUCCCGGGCGCGUUGCCGCCCAGUCCCGGGGACCGUCCCUACCGCGAGGGUCUGAGGCGCGGCUGCCCCGGGGAGGGUGGAAGGCCAGGCGUGGGGCCCGAACCUCUGGCUGACUUUGGCAGGGCCCAUCUGGCACGGCCUCCGCGGCGCGCAGGUCCCAGAAGAGAAGCCCCUGAGGGCAGGCACCCGGUCUCAUCUGUGUUUACAUCCUAAGUGCGCAGGCUGGGCUCCGAUAAGUGCUGACUGGCCAAGGUCAGAGGGUGCCAGCUGGCUACGUCGUUGGAGAACAGAGCCACAUGUCUUUCAAUCUGGUCUCCUAGAGAAGUGCUGAGAGGGGAGCAACAGCCAGAGAAGUCCCGGGGUCUGGUGACAGUGCUUGGUCCCAUCCAUGGGCCUGGGAGCCCCAUCUUGGAUUCUCUCCGACCUCCCAGCCCUUUUAAUCAAAAUCUUUUGGGCCGAAGGAAUUUGUAGCCACCAACUCUGCAGGAGAAAAUGUCGUCAGUGAAGAGUGGGCUGGCCUGGGCAUGCCUCUGGGCCAGCCUGGGCGUCUAUACCAGAAUGCUGCCUCUGCUGAGGGAGGUCUGCCUGGCAGCACCAUCCCCACAUCCACAGCCUCAGACAAGUGCUCCCUUCCUGGGCCUGAUUUGGAGUAUCGGGGGUAUCCUGAUUUGGAGUAUCAGGGGGUAUCCGAUUUGGAGUAUCAGGGAGUAUCCUGAUUUGGAGUAUCAGGGGGUAUCCUGAUUUGGAGUAUCAGGGGGUAUCCUGAUUUGGAGUAUCAGCGGGUAUCCUGAUUUGGAGUAUCAGGGGGUAUCCUGAUUUGGAGUCAGAGCCAUCCCCAAGGCUGUAAGUGGCGGGCGCCUGGCUGCAGAUGGUGACUCCUCCUGCCUCAGGAGUCAGGGAUACAGCAGCUCUGGGGGUGCCUGUGGCCACUGCCAGGCAGUGGGGCCAGAUCAGCUGCAUGCGUCUGUUUUGCUCUUUGGAAACUCCUGCAAGGUGUAGGGUUGUUCAGGUUUGGGGAUGGCAAAAGGAGAGCCAGAAUUUAGGAAUCCAAAUUAAUGGAUUCCUUUCAAAGUAAUUGCCCUGGUGAUGGUGUCACUGGGGAGCUGAUGUGCAAGCCACAGAGAUUGGCCCCAGAGCAGAACCAUCCAACCCAAUCAUAUUCACAGGGCUUGACCUGAUGACCUUUGACAAUUCCACAAUACAAGGACAAAGAUUUGCUAUCUUUGGGGACAUGCAAAAGAAAGUGAGGGCUGGGAUAGUGGGUCAUGCAUGUAAUCUCAGUGCUUUGGGAGGAUAAAGUGGGAAGAUCGCUUGAGCCCAGGAGUUGGAGACCAGCCUGGGCAACAUAGUGGGACUGUCUCUGCAAAAAUAAAAAAUAAAUAGCUAGGCAUGGCAACACGCCGCUGUAUUUCUAGCUACUCAGGAGGCUGAGGCAGGAGGAUCACUUGAGCCCAGGAGAUUGAAGCUUCAGUGAGCUAUCAUUGCGCCACGGCACUCCAGCCUGGGUGACAGCGCAAGACCCUGUUUCAAAAACAAAAAACAAAACAAAACAAAGCAAGGCCGGGCACGGUGGCUCACGCCUCUAAUCCCAGCACUUUGGGAGGCCAAGGCUGGCGGAUCUCUUGAGUCUGGAGUCCAGGAGUUGGAGACCACCCUGGGCAACAUAGUGGGACCCUGUCUUUACAAAAAAAUAAAAUAAAGUAGCCAGGUGUGGUGGUGCGUGCCUGUACUUCCAGCUACUCUGGAGGCUGAGGUGGGAGGAUCACUUGAGCCCAGGAGGUCAAGGUUACAGUGAGCUGUGAUGGUGCCACUGCACUCCAGCCUGGGCAACAGAGCAAGAUCCUGUCUCAGAAGAAAAAAAAAAACCCUAAACCCAAAACCCAAAUACCACCAGUUGAAUCCCUGGGGGAAAACUAAGUCCUCCAUUUAGCUUUGAGAUGGGACAACUCAGAGGUCACUUCAAAUAAUGCUUGGCUUGGCCUGCAGGAGGCUCUGAGCCUCAGGUGGGCUGAAGGGCAGGGUGGCUAGGAGUGAGUGUCUGGCAGUCAGGGUGGUAGCCAGCCGGCAGAGGGAGAUGGGCUGCGGGAGGCAUGGGUUCACGACCCUGCAGAAAGAGGGCAGGGCUGGAUGGAUGGAAGGCAGGAGAAAGCAGGCCAGAUGGCUUAGGGUGGACCAGGAUUCCACACCAUUUACUGUGCCCACGUUUCCUUUUAUUUCAGCUGUUUUCAAGUCAGCAAACAUUUACUGAGGAUCUACUAUGUACAAGAUGAACAUCUGCAACAAGCCCUCCAACAAGACGGCCCCUGAGAAGAGUGUGUGGACGGCACCGGCACAGCCCAGCGGACCCUCCCCUGAGCUGCAGGGCCAGCGAUCCCGCCGGAAUGGGUGGAGCUGGCCCCCUCACCCGCUCCAGAUUGUGGCCUGGCUGCUGUACCUCUUCUUUGCUGUGAUCGGCUUUGGGAUCCUUGUUCCCCUCCUGCCUCACCACUGGGUGCCCGCUGGCUACGCUUGCAUGGGCGCCAUCUUUGCUGGCCACCUUGUGGUGCACCUGACCGCCGUCUCCAUCGAUCCAGCAGAUGCCAACGUGCGGGACAAGAGCUAUGCGGGGCCCCUGCCCAUCUUCAACCGAAGCCAGCACGCACAUGUCAUUGAAGACCUGCACUGCAACUUGUGCAACGUGGAUGUGAGCGCUCGCUCCAAGCACUGCAGCGCCUGCAACAAGUGCGUGUGCGGUUUCGACCACCACUGCAAGUGGCUCAACAACUGUGUGGGCGAGCGGAACUACCGGCUCUUUCUACACAGUGUUGCAUCCGCUUUACUGGGCGUCCUGCUCCUGGUGCUGGUGGCCACAUAUGUCUUCGUGGAGUUCUUUGUCAACCCCAUGCGUCUGCGCACCAACCGACACUUUGAAGUCCUGAAGAAUCACACGGAUGUGUGGUUCGUGUUCCUGCCUGCCGCCCCCGUGGAGACCCAGGCCCCUGCCAUCCUGGCCCUGGCCGCCCUGCUCAUCCUUCUGGGCCUCCUGUCCACAGCCCUCCUGGGGCACCUGCUCUGCUUCCACAUUUAUCUCAUGUGGCACAAGCUCACCACCUAUGAGUACAUCGUGCAGCACCGCCCACCACAGGAGGCCAAGGGGGUUCACAGGGAGCUCGAGUCAUGUCCUCCCAAGAUGCGGCCCAUUCAGGAGAUGGAGUUCUACAUGCGGACCUUCAGACAUAUGCGCCCAGAGCCCCCUGGCCAGGCCGGGCCAGCAGCAGUGAAUGCCAAACACUCUCGCCCUGCCUCCCCGGAUCCGACCCCAGGUAGGAGGGACUGUGCUGGGCCUCCGGUCCAGGUGGAGUGGGAUAGAAAGAAGCCUCUACCCUGGCGCUCGCCUCUGCUUCUUUUGGCGAUGUGGGGCCCUCAGGCUCCCCCGUGUCUCUGCAGAAAAAGAGGAAGAGGCGCGUGUAUAAAGUGCGAACGUCUGAGACCUCGGAUCCGGCGUCGGGGCCUAGGGCCCCCAGCCGCCGCUCCAGCUCGUCGACGGAUUCCGCGGACGCCAGCCCUGUGCACGCCGCUGGCCCUGCCGGCGCCUACCACUCGGCGUCGGCAGAGUCCGUGGACGAGAUUCCAGUGGCGCAGACGCGCCUGGGCAGCGCCGCUCUGGCCGCCCCGCGGGGCCGGGGCCGACAGCCCACGCUGGCGCGGCAGGCGCGUGCGCCCGCCGUUUUCGUGAGCCCGAGCAGCGGCGAGCCCAGGGCGCCGGGCGGCCGGGAGGCUGGUCUGGCUUAGCUGGGCCGAGAGGCCGGAGGGCCGAGUUAGAGCGGCCGGCCUGACUCUCUAUGCAACACCCCAUCCUUGCCGCACCGAGUGCACUUUAGGGGCCCCUACGGCCGGCGGGAUCGGCCUCCCUCCCCCACGACUCAGCAAUACCCGCCCCACCGGCUGUGAUGCUCCAAUAAACUUUUUUAUGCUUUUGCGGACGUCGCGCUUACUUUCUUAAUGGCAGGGGCCACGGGCCAUCCAGAAGCCCGACCCUGGCCAGUGGACCGGGGGCGGGGAGGAGGUCCCUGUAUAGUAGGUAGCCACCCAGGCUGCCCUGUGGAGGUGCUCACGUGCGGCUCGUGGUUAGGAAAGGCCUUAGAAGGCGGCCUGGAGGAGGUUAUUUUUCUUAAAGAUGGGCUUUGCACUGGGAGGCCGAGAGAAAGCAGGCUUUGGGCUCCGAAAGCAGCAGUGGGCGCUGAGGCUGC